AGCCUCUUCCGGCAACCAUUAAAGGGCACGGUUGCUAGGGAGACGCGGCGGUAACCUGGACCUUAAAAGUUUGUUGUCGUUAGGGAAUAGGUGGGAAUAUGGUUGUGGGAUUAAUGAAACACAGUACCAAAGAGAUUCCAGAAAGAGAACUGGUGUAGGAAUAGGGCCUGCAUGGGAGGAGUUCAAAGAUGCUUCUUGGAGGGAGCCGAUAACCCGCGGGUGGAGCCUACCCGAGACAGGGCAUCACUGUGUUGCCAAGGCUGGUCUUGAACUGGCUCAAGCAAUCUGCCCACCUCGGUCUCCCAAAGUGCUGGGAUUACAGGAGUGAGCCACUGCGCCCUGCCUGAAAUUGAACACAAAUGUGGUGGAGACGGGACAGGGCAGGUGGAAAUUCACUUAUAAGUCCUGAUUGGCUAAGCCCUGGUCACGAGACCGUAAAAGAGCAACGUCUGUCUCAGAGCGACUCCCACAGCGUCCUUAGCAACCAGCCUUGGUUCCCAGCGGCUCAGAGCGCAGCGAACUCAUCUGAAAGACUUUUAUAAAUGACAGUGCAUCAACAGUUGAGCAUGUGUUAACGUGGAGUGGUAUAUUAAUAGAAAGAAGCAUAAUAUAGCACAAAGCACUCAGUCAAGCUUCUAGUCCAGAAAGCGUAUGAUUUUAUCUGAAGUAAUUUGGAAUAAAUUUACUUGAAGGCAAGGUAUUCUAUAUGAGAAGUUAGGCCAAAUGUUGAUUUGGACAAAAGUGAAUGUAGUAAAAUGGGAAAAAAAUCCUGAAGGCUGGCAUCAAAAUAACUCUUAAACAAUGAACUAUUACAGAGAUUUCCACUUGAGUCAUGACUCAUGCCAUCUUCCCCUCAAGUGCAACAUAAGAAUUUAUGAUUUAUGAAUAUGCCUGUUAACAAAUCACCUAUGAUUAAUACAUGUGGAGGCAUAUCUUCCCCUUAUCAUGAAGAGCUCUGGAAAUUAAAUUUUCAACAUUUAAGUGGAGAAAGGGGUCAUAAAUCAAGGCCAACAUUUUCAAUCACAAAAGAAUUCAUCUUGAGAUUCAAUCAAACACAAAAUUCCAAAGAGAAGGAAGAAUUGUUGGAACUAGCUAGAAAAAUCAUUCUCAGAUGUAAGAGAAAAUUGGGUCUCAAAACCCUGGGCUCUGGAAGGCAUGUGCAUCUUCCUGCUGCAUGGACUGAAGUAAUAUAUCUGGCUCAAUGCAAAGGGGAAAUCCAAGAUGAAUCUUUAAAUAUGCUUUAUGCAUCUCUGGACCAUGCUUCCUUUGAUUAUGAUCAUCUGCCUGCCUUAUUUUUUGUUGCGGAAUCGGUUUUAUACAGACUGUGUUGUGAUGCAUCCCUCAAAACAUAUUUAUAUUCAGUUGAAAUAAAGCUAGCAAAGAUUGGCUAUUUGGUCUUCUUACGACUUUUUAUAUUUUUCCUGCAUGGUCAUCUAGAAAGUUUUAAACAACAUUUACUUAGGCUUCAACCAUAUUUAUACGCACUUUCUUUCUCUGGAGCAUCAUAUCACAAGUAUCCAAACAUCUUUUCAAAUGUGCAAUUCAUCCUGAAAGCCUCGGAAAUUAUAGGUAAAAGAGAACUCCGUUCUGAAUCCAUUUUUAGACCUGUGGAAGAUAAGAAAAGAUAUGAGAACACAGAUUCUGAUAUGGGAGGAUAUGAAAUUAACCACCUGCUCUGGCACUGUGUUGCUGCUUGGUCUUGUGUUCAGAAUAACAGUCCUCAGUUGAAUAACGUGCUUGAACAUCUCGUCUUCCAUAAGACACAGCUUCAAAAGAAAUGCUGGUUGGAUUCAGUACUGGCUUUACUGGUCCUUGGGGAGGCUGCCAAAUUAAACAUGGCCUGCUUGAAAGCUUUAAUGGACGUAGUGAGAGAUUUUGUUUCAAGCAUUAUGUCUGUUCAAAAUCAGGAAGAAAGUUGCAAGGUAGAUGAUUUUUCCUGGGCCUGGAAUGUAGUCUACAUAUAUACAGUAAUUCUUGCAGAAAUCUGCUUGUAUGCAGCCACUUCUGAUUUGCGAAAAACUGCUUUAAUUGGUUUCUGUCACUGUAAAAGUUCACAAAAAAAUAUUUUAUACUUGGACAAAUCAGUACCUCCAGAAUUAAAGGAAACAAGUAUUUUAAGUCUUUUGGAAUAUUUCUCUUCAAAAAUGUCAGAGAACUGUGAUCAAGUAGUCUGGACUGGUUACUAUGGCUUAGUGUAUAACCUGGUGAAAAUUUCAUGGGAACUUCAAGGAGACGAAGAACAGGAUGGACUUAGAAACAUGAUAUGGCAAACAUUGCAGAAAACAAAGGAUUAUGAGGAAGAUGUACGAAUCCAAAAUGCAAUCAAUAUAGCUCAGGCUGAGUUAAAUGACCCAACUGAUCCUUUCACUAGAUAUAGUACAAAUAUUUCAUCAAAUGUAGGAGAAGAAGUUUUCUCCAAAUAUAUUGGGUGGAGAAUUGCCAACACUCUUUCCAAACUAUUCUUUCCCCCCAUUGAGGCCCAUUUUCUUCCUUUGAAGAAACCAUCAAUAAAAAAGGAUCAAACAAAAUAUCCAAAUAAAAAGCUGGAGUCUGUGAAAAAGCAAGUUCUACAUUUCACUGUAAGGUACUACCAUAAUAUGAAAAAGAUCCAUGGUUAAAGAUAGUUUGGUGCUUUUUAUGGAAGUGCAACCAUCUACGGUUAACCAAGCAUUUUUCCCAGUGGGAAAUGGAAACCAUUUAUUUCUAUUUUCUGUAGAAGUUACAUUAAUGCCAAAAUAGUGGUAUGUAUUCAGUUGAAUAUGUUUAGAAUAAUGUGUUUCAUUUAGCAAUGCCAGUUCUUUAACAUCUGAAACAGGCCUCAGGUUUGUUUUGAAAAACCUUGUCUAAAUAUUAAAAUAGAGCCCAGUCAUACAGUUAAUUUAUUCCCAAAAGGAGAUCUGAUUUCACAUACCGUUUUUGUCCCAUUUGCUGGCUGUCUUAAUACUAAGGGAAUUUCAUGUUUCUAAACACCAUCUACGUUAUCAUCCUCUGUCUGUUGGUGUUAUAAGGGCCAAGAAAUCUGAAAAUUAAAAUCGUAACCUUUUUCAAAAUACAAGAAAUAAGGUAACUAAUAAAGCUGUUAUUUUUCACAAAAAUGCAAAUCAAGCACACACAUUCCUCCCACCAUUCAUAAAAACAUUAGAAUGUCCAAACGUGCUGUAAUAAUUACAUCUGGGAAAUGCUAGCAGACUUGAGGUACUGUUUGUCAUUAGGUUGUUCAUUACCAUGAUUAUUCAUAGGCAAUCCACUGUCAACUUAAUUCUUUGUAUGAAUAGAAGAUCUAGAAUCAUUACAAUAACAUUUUUCUAUAUUAAUCACAAAUCCAUUUUUUUGGAAUUUUAUUAUGAACUCUAUAUUUCAGGAUCACAUACAUUAGUUGGCUAGGGAUACCAUAACAAAAUCAGUAUGGGAUACUGAAACAAGAGAAAUUUAUUUACUCAUGGUUCCAGAUGCUGGAAGUUCAAGAUAAAGGGGUUGGCAGGUUUGUUUUCCUCUGGAGUCCUUUUCUUUGACUUGUAAAAUAGCUGCCUUCUGGCUGUACCCCUCACAGGUCCUUUUCUCUGUGCUCACACACCUGUUGUUAUUUUUGUAUCAAAAUUUCCUUUUAAGGACACCAGUCAAGUUGGAUGAGACCCCAUCCAUAUGACUUCAUUUAACAUUAAUUACCUUUUAAAAGCCCCAUCUCCAGGUAGAGUCACAGCAUAAGAUACUGUGAAUUAGGGCUGCAGAAUAUUAAUUAUAGGGGAACAAAAAGCAGCCCAUAACAUAUACUAGUAAUAUUUCCUUUCAAUUAUGACAUUAUAUAUUAAAAAAACUAAAGAAUUCAGUGUUGAAAUGGGUUGCCCAACAAUACCUACAGAGUUAGUAAUAAAGCCAUAUUAAUAUAUGGUCUUUAUCAAAGACAACAAAAACGAUUCUGUGUUGAAAGUGUUCUGUCAAUUUUAUUCUUUUGUCCCAUUACUGAGGAAAAAUCUAAGUACUCUACCUGAUGUCUGUGAACUAUGAAAUUUUCCACUUUGGUUAGAAAUUGAUUUUUCCGGCCCUGUGUGAACCUCAAGGAUUGUUUGCUGUACUUUUUUUUAGUGGUUCUUUCCCCAGACCCUGGUAGUGUCCUCAGGUGCUUGUGCUGCAAUUAAUGAGUACUCAGCUGAGUGGGGAACUCUGGAUAUCUGCAGAGUUCUUUCUCUGGGAGGCUUUCACCUGAACUCUCUACUACCUUGCAAACAAACUAGCCACUUUGGCCUCCUUGUACUUAUAGCUCUAUCUCUUCACUUCAGGAAUUUGCUGAGCUCCAUCUAGAUUCUCCUAGCUUUGGAGAUUGGCAGUUUUCCCUGGUUAGUAAGCUGAGACAAUUGGACCUCAUUUGUUUGCCAUUUUUGGAGAUUUUUAUCCUUCACUGUUUGAUGUCCAAUAUAUUGAGAACUGGUUUUUGUAAAAAAAAAAAAAAAAAAAAAAAAUCAAAGUAUAAAUAGAAAUCUGUUACUCCCUCUUGACUAAAAGCUAUCAUUCAUAUUUAAAAGUACAAUCUGUCAGGGAUGAAAUUUUAUAUAUGGUGUUCCAUAGGCAUCAAAAGUUUUCUUCCUAAUAGAUAUCCAGUGCAUCCAGCCUCAGUUACUUUCACUAAAAAUAUAGCCUUUCCUUUUCAGAAAAAAAAUACAGGCUUUCCUCAUAGCACUGCAGGAUCACUUUUGUCAUAAAUCAAGAAUUGGCAUAACUGUAUAUAUUUGGGUCUGUUGCUGGACUCUCUAUUGUUCCAUUGGUCUACUUCCUUACACUAAUACCAUAAUUUUAAUUUAUGUGACUGUGUGAUGAAUCUUAAUAAAAUAUUUGGGCUUCUACUUCAAGAUUGUUUUAGGGCUCUUCAGGACUUUUGAAUUUUUACACAAAUAUUAGCAUCUAAUAUUUAAAUGUUGAAUCUAGGAACUAAUUUGGGAAAAAUACUGCACUGAAAAAUUGUUUCAAUACUAUAUUGAAAAAUAUGUAUCUUUUGGUCUAUGAUCAUAGUAUAGUCUUCAGUUCACUGAAGUGUUCUUUUAUUUCUGACAAUAUUCAGUGUAGAAAUUGUAAUAAUUUUUCAUUAGCAUUAUUUGUUUUUUCUUGAUGUUUUUCAAAUGACAUCUUUUAAAUUUUUAUUUGCUAUUUCUUGCUAAUACAAAGAAAUAGCAAUGAUUUUAUAUAUUAACUGUUUCUAUAGCAACUUAUUAAAUAUGCAUAUUAAGUCUAAUUAUUUAUAAGUGGGUAUCUUUAUUUUCUAAGUAUAAAAGUCACUAAGGAUAACAAUUUUUUCUGUUCUUUAAAAUUCCAAUAUGUAUGCCUUUUAUGUCCUUGCCUUUCCUCAUUGUGCUAGCUAGAACUUCUAAUUUAUAGUUAGAUAGAAGUGAUCAUAGUGUACAUUUCUUGAAUCAUUCCCAAUAUCAUGGGUAAAGGUCUGAGUAAAUCACCAUUAAAGGUGAUAUUAGCUGUAGGUUUUUUUUCCCAAGAAUAUGUAAAAUGAGAAUUGGAGUUUAAAAACAGAACAGGGAUACAUUAAACAAUUAGCUGUAGGUUUUAAAAAAUCUUUACCAGGUUAAGAAGUAACUUCUAGCCAUAAUUUGCUAAUAUUUUAAAAGUUUCAUUGUAUUUUUAAUUGACAUAUAAUAAUUGUACAUAUUUAUGGGGUACCAUGUGACAUUUCAGUGUAAGUACAUGUUAUAUAAUGAUCAAAUCAGGGUAAUUAGCAAAUCAUUUAUCUCAAACAUUUAUUUGUGAUGAGAACAUUCAGAAUCCGUUCUUAUAGCUAUUUUGAAAUGUACAAUGUAUUUUUGUUAACUAUAGUCACUAUAUUGUGCAAUGGAACACCACAAUUUACUUAUUUUAUCUAGCUGUAACUUUGUGUACCUAUUGAUCAACCUCUCCCCAUUUCUCUCUACCCCCUACUCUCCCCCACCCCCAGCCUAUGAUAGUAACCACUUUUGAUUUCACACAGGAGUAAGUUAUUUUGCGGGUUUUUUUUUUUUUUUUUUUUUUUUUUUUGGUGUCUGGCUUAUUUCACUUAACAGAAUGUCCUCCAGGUUUAUCUAUGUUAUUGCAUAUCAUAGAAUUUCCUCUUUUUUUUUGAAUUUGACUAGUAUUCCAUUGGGUAUAUAUAUUAUAUUUUCUUUAUUCAUUUUUUCCAUUGAUCGACACUUACAUUGAUUCUAUAUCUCAGCUAUGGUGAAUAGUGCUGCAAUAAACAUGGGAGUGCAGAUAUCUAUUUGACAUAAUGAUUUCCUUUGAAUAUAUACCCAGUAGUGAGAUUGCUAGAUCAUGUGGUACUUCAAUUUUUUUUUUAAUUUUUUAAUUUUUAAUUUUUGAGAGUACAUAGUAGGUGUAUACAUUUAUUAUUUUCAAUAUUUUAGAAACCUCCAUAAUAUUUAACAUAAUGACUGUACGAAUUUAUAUUCCUACCAACAGUGCAUAAGGGUUCCCUUUUCUUCACAUCCUUGGCAACACUUAUCUUUUGUUUUUUAGAUAACUUUGCAUUUUAUCUGGAGGGCGGUGAUAUCUCACUGUGGUUUUGAGUUGCAUUUUCCUGAUGAUCAGUGAUGUUGAGUAUUUUUAUGUAACUUUUGGGCAUUUGUAUGUCUUCUUUUGAAAAAUAUCCAUUCACAUAUUUUGCCCAUUUUUAAUCCAUUUUGUUUGUUAUUGAGUUGUUUCAGUUUCUUGUAUAUUCUGGUUAUUAACCUCUUGUCAGAAGUAUAGUUUGCAAAAAUUUUCUCCCAUUCGACAGGUUGUCUCUUCACACUGUUGGUGGUUUUCUUAGCUGUGUAGAAGUUUCUUAGUUUGAUAUGUUUGAUAUAAUCUUAUUUGUCCUUUUUUUUUUUUGCAUUUGUUGCCUGUGCUUUUUAGGUUUUAUCCAAAAAAAUCUUUGCCCAGACCAAUAUUAUAUAGCAUUUACUCUAUGUUUUAUUCUGGUUUUUUCAUAGUUUCGAGGUCUUACAUUUAACUCUGUAAUGCAUUUGGAGUUAAUUCCUUACAUAUGAGAGAUAGGGGACAAAUUUUAUUCUUCUGAAUGUAGACAUUCAAUUUUCCAACCAUCAUUUAUUGAAAAGACUGUCCUUACCCCAGUAUGAGUUUUUGGCCCGUUUGGCAAAAAUAAGUUGGCUUAAGAGCUAUGGGUUUAUUUCUGGGCUCUCUAUACUGUCCCAUUGGUCUAUGUAUUCAUUUUUAUGUCAACACCAUGCUUUUUUUGUUAUUAUAGCUUUGUAGUAUAUUUUGAAGUUAGGUAGUGAGAUGCCUUCAGCUGUGUUGUUGUGUUUAUUUGGUUUUGGUUUUGUUUGCUCAAGAGUGCUUUGAUUUACAGAGUCUUUUGUGGUUCAAUAAAAAUUUUAGGAUCCCUAUUUUUUCUAUUUCUGUAAAGAAUUCAUUGGUAUUUUGAUAGGUAUUGCAUUGACUCACUCUGCAGAAUAAUUUUGGGAGUAUGGACUUUUUAACAAUACUAAUUCUUCCACUGCAUAUACACAGGAUAUUUUUUCCAUUUAUUUAUGUCCACUUCAAUUUUUAUAAUCAGUGUUUUAUAGUUUUUGUUUUGGAGAUUUUUUACCUCCUUAGUUAAAUUUAUUCCAAGGUAUCUUAUUUUUUGUAGUUAUUGUGAAUGGAGUUGUUUGCUUUUAUUUCUUUUUCAGAUAGUUCAUCAUUAGCAUGUAAAAAUGCUACCAAUUUUUUAUGUUGAUUUUGUAUCCUGAAACUUUACUGAAUUUGUUUAUUAGUUAUAAUAGUUUUUUGUGGAGUCUUUGGCUUUUCUAUAUAAGAUCACAUCUCCUGCAGAUCAGGACAGUUCGACUUCCUCCUUUCCUAUGUGGAUGCAUUUUCUUUCCUUCUUUAGUCUAACUGUUCUGGCUAAAACUUCCUGUAAUAUGUUGAAUAGAAGUGUCUAGGAACUUAUCUCUUUCUUCUAGGUUUCCCAAUUUGUAGGUGUAUAGUUGUUCAUAGUAGUAGUCUUUUAUGAUCCUUUCCAUUUCUGUGUUAUAUGUUGUAAUGUCUUCUUUUUCACCUUUGAUUUGAUUUCUUUGAGUCUUCUCUCUUUUUUGACUUCUUAGUCUGGCUUAAAGUUUGUUGGUUUGUUUAUCUUUUCUGAAAAACAACUUUGUUUCUACUCAAAGGACUGUCAUAGUCAUGUUUUGUAGGUUAGCUCUAGUAGUGAUAAAUUUCCUCAACUUUUGCUUGUCUGGAAAAGAUUUUAUUUCUCCUUUCUCAUUAAUGAAGGACUGGUCUGCUAGGUAUAGAAUUCUUGGCUGCCAGGUUUUUUUUGUCUUCUUUUUUUUUUUCUUUCAGCACUUGGAAUAUGUCAUCCCAUUCUCUCCUGGACUACACAGUGUCUGCUGUGAAGUUCACUGAUAUCAUAAUGGAAUUCCUUUAUAUGUGACUCUGCUUUUUUCUUGCUGUCUUUAAAAUCCUCUCAUUGUCUUUGACUUUUGAGGGUUUAAUUAAUGUCUCUAAGUGAAGUCCUCUUUGGUUUUAAUCUGCUUGGGGACCUUUGAGCUUCAUCUAUCUGGAUUUCCAUAUCUCUUCAAACACUUGGGAAGUUUUCACCAAUUAUUUUAUUAAGUAAGUUUUCUGUCUGCAUCUUUCUCUCUUUUCCUUCUGGAAUUCCCAUAAUACAAAUGUUUGUUCAUUUAAUGCUGUCCCAUAAGUCUUGUAUACUGUCUUCACUGUUUUUCAUUCUUAUGUUUUUCUUUCUUCUGACUUGGUAAUUUCAAAUGACCAGUCUUCAAGUUCAGAGAUUCUUUCUUUUGCUUUAUUUAGUCUCAACUGUAUUUUUUGAAGCUCUCUAUUGUACUUUUUUAUUUUAUUCAUUGAAUUCUUCAACUCCAAUAUUUCUGUGUGGUUGUUUUUAAUGAUGUCUAUCUCUUUGGUAAGGUUAUCAUUUAGAUCAUGAAUAGUUUUCCUGGUUUAACCAAAUUGUCUAUCUGUAUUAUCUUGUAUCUCACUGAGUUUCCUUAAGGUCAUUAUUUUGAAUUUCUUUUCUGGCAAUUUGUAGAUUUUCAAUUCUUUGGGACCUGUUACUGGACUACUAUUGUGCUCCUUUGGUGGUGUCAGAUUUUCUUGAUUUUUCAUUGCUUUUUUGUGUCUCUGUGUUGAUGUCUGUGCAUCUGGUGUAACAAUCACCACUUCUAAACUUUAGAAAGUGGCUUUCAUAGAGAAAUACUUUCACCUGAAAAUGGGUCUUAAUGUCCUGGUUAGGAAGGGUGUGCUGACUCUGGUUCUAAGUUGCAAUCAACAUCAGCAAUAACUGGGUACCUCAGUGGCCUAUGCUGUAGGAGUUUGUAGGAGUGAUGGUGGCAGCACAAGUUAUUAGGGUCCUCAGUGGCAAGAGUUUAUAUCGUCCUCUUAUUUUUUUAUUUCCCACAAUGGGGAGACUAAGCCAAGGAAAUUUCCCUUGGUGCUGUGUCUGACUUGGUUCCUAAGCAGCUGCAGCAUGCUGGGUUCCAGGGCACAGAUGUUUACAGUGGCUAUGAAGCAGGGGUUCCAGGUCAGUGUCUUGUGAACUUUUUGUGGCACCUGGGCUUUUACAUACAAGUUCAUUCUCUGUGGUCGGGUAGAAUGUGGAUUCCUCACAGAACCAUGGUCUGUGACUGUGAGGCAUCUUCUAGCGCUUGUGCCCAGGGAACAAGGUUGUAGCUAUAACUCUGACCCUACGGGCAGGGCACAGCACAGGCCCGUCCCUGGGGAAGAGAAGGUUUUCUAGAUGUUUGGGUCCAGGGAGCACGGUACAGCUGCACUGCAUGAAACAGAACCAACAAGGUUCAUUAGAAACUCAGGUCUCAGGGGAUGAGGCACUGUGUAGCAGUGACUCUGGACCCUGGGAUAGUUAGACUUGGCAGUAUCCCAAACUCUGUGAAGCCAGAUGCAGCAGGAGUACGAACUCCAACAUGGUAGAGUAUGGCUGUUGCUGGGGUUCCGGGGGGGCAGGGAGCAUCACAGUAAUGACUCCACUCUUUGGCAAAGAAAAUGUCCAGCAGCUCAAAUUUUAGGGGACUAUUCCAACUUCAGGGAAGCAGAGUGUUAGAGUUUUAUGGACUGUAAGGCAGGGUGUCUCAGCUCAGCCACUACAUUUUUUCCCCUGGGACAUAGAAUGCUCUAUCAGUGCAAUCGUGGUGUACAUAGCUGCUCCGCUUAGCCAACGCACUGAUUCCCUGGAAGGCAAUGUGUCAUUUCAGCUCAGGCUGAGGGGAUUGACAGCUCUGGGUGGCUAAGGCACUGUUUCCCCUGGAUACAGAGCAUCACCUCAGUGCUGACACGGGAACAGGGUGCAGCAGCAACUAGGAGGGAUAUAUCAAUCAGCUCCACCAAGGCACCAUUUCCCUAGGAGGGAAUGCACAGCUUUAGCUCAGGUUCCAUGGUUCAGAGUGCAGCAGUGGCUUGGAGAGGGGUAGAUAGGGUGGCUUCACCAAGGCACCAUUUCCCCAGGAGGAAUGUGUAACUUCAGCUUGGUCUCUGAGGAGGCAGGGCACAGCCAUGACUGGCAUGAGUAGGUGGCAUGGCUUCAGGGGUGCUUGGCCGCAUUUGGUAGGGUAUAACAGCAGUUCACAGCCCAGCUCAGAGAUACUGGACUACCAGACAAGCAUGAUUUAGUGGCUGCUAAGCCUCAGGGAUGGGAGAUUUCCAUGGCUACUCAAUCUGUAGCAAGACACAUGCCAGCCAUAGUUCCAGUUCCAAAAUGGUAUGGUGUAAAAGCUCUGCAGGCCACUGAGCGAGGGGCACAGUAUUGGCUGUUUGUUUCUAUGGGGGAAGCACAAAUGUAUGGACUCCAGACAGCUCCCUUAGCUGGACUUCAUUCUCAUGAGGAUUGCUGAAGACCCCAGUGGUGAGAACUUUAGGUUCCAAAAUGUUGAUUGGGGCUGCUGGGAUCCUAUUGCUUACUUUUUCCCCACAGAGAGAAGUUCCUCCUGGUUUCAAGCUUAUUCUGGUUUAGGGAUGAAUUAGUGAAGGCCAGGUAUUUUCUUUUGUUCUCUAUGUUUCUAGAGUUUUUGUGCUCUACAUGGUUUCUGGUACUCCUUUGACAUAUUCCAGUACUCUCCUUUAGUUAUUUUUAUCCAAAUAUAGUUGUUAAUUGUUUCUGCUGACUUUGUGGUAGUUACAAGAACUAAGGGCUUCUAGACAGCCAUCUUACUGACAUUAUUCCUAAGAUUUUUUUAUUAUUAUGAAAGGAUCUGGGAUUUGAGCAAAUAUGUUCAUUCAUCUAUUAAGAUGAUUAUAUAAUUUUAUUAAACUGGUAAAUUUUUCAUCACAAAUUAACCUUGCUUUCCUGGGGUUAUACUUAUAUAAUCAUGACAUAUUGUGGUUUUUAUAUAUCAUUCGAAUAGAAUUUCCAAUGUUUCAUUUAACAUUAUCACAUCCCUGUUUAUAAGAAAUAUAAUUAUUAGCCUUUCCUUUUACAUUGAUAUUUAAAGUUAUAAAUUUAUUUAAGGCAAGCUUUUAUUUAGGGCUAUAAAUUUCCCUCUAACAACCUUAGUUCAUCAUUUUAUAGUAGUAUGUCUAUACUCUCAGUUUAAAAUAGUUUCAAAAUUUUCAUGUAAUGUUUUUAAGCGUUUAAUCAAGGUCUGCUAGUAAUAAAUUCUUUAAACUUUUUAUGUUAAAAAAACAUUAUUUUAUGCUCUUAUAUGAAAUAUAUUUAUUUAUUUUCACUGGGAAGAUAAUUUUGGAUUGGUGAUUAUUUUCUUUCAAAAUUUAAAAGAUGUUAUUUCAUUGUAUUCUGGGUUCCAUUAUUCCUGUUGAGAAGUUAGCUGUAAUAUAUCUUUUUUUUAUUUUAAAGUAAAGUAAUGUAUCUAUCUUUUUUUUUCUUCCAAUGAAUAUCCCUUGUUGUGGGUUGAAUUGUGUUCCCCUGAAAUUAUGCUGAAUUGGAAUGGGCCCCUAUUCCCAUAUGACUGGUGUCCUUAUAAAAAGUGGGGAUUGGCCACAAAUAUGCACACAGGAAGAAUGUCAUGUAAAGGUAAAUCCACAUAUCAGGGUGAUGCACCCAAAGCCAAAGAGUAUAGAAGAUUCCCAAAACAAACAACAAAAGAACCCUGCUAGACUAGAAUCUUGGAUAGAAGAACCUUGGGAUGUGUUUCUCUCUUAUAGCUCACAGAAGGAGCCAUGUGGACACAUUGAUCAUGGAAUUCUAGCUUCCAGAACUGUGUGAAAAUAUAUUUUUAUUUAUUUUUGAAUCUACCCAAUUUGUGGUACUUUUUAAUGGCAGUCCUAGCAAACUAAUAGAAAUAUUAUUUGAAUAUUUUUAUCUUUCACUUUCAGUAGUCUUAAUAUGAUGUAUAUAGGCGUAAAUUUUUAUGUAUUUGUUGUAUCUUUUGUUUGCAAAGCUUUUUGAAAUAUUUCAUGAGUUCUGGAUAUGAUGGCUUUCAUAGUUUUGAAGCUAUUCUGCAAAUGCAGUUUUUAUUCUUAGUGGCUUUCUGUUAGUGUAUUAGCUGCCCAACUGCAUAAGCUUUAGAAUUUGAAAGAACUCUUCAAAGAAAAACUGGCUGAAUUUUGAAACUCAUCCGUUAUUCAGUUUUAUCUCAUCAGCCUUAGAACACCACCAUCUCUCCUAAUUUCUCUGUUCUCUACCAGGAGGCUCCUACCUGGGAAAAGCCUAGAUUUUUAGUCACAUAUUCUGCAGGCAGAACUGACAAAUUAAAUGGAGAAAAGUAUCCUAGGGGAGGGUUAGCCUACCUCUCUAUGGUUCUGUUCCUUUGAAAACCUUUUUUAUCCAGUCUUCAUGAUUUCAGCAUCACAAUGAUGUCUUUAGCCAGAUGAAUUAUGUAAGCAUAUUUUUCCAACUUUAUUGGUAGACAUAUUGGUCUGCCGUCCAUCUUCUUUAAAUUUUUUUUCUGAUUAUAACCAUAAUAUAUAUAUUUCAUAAAAUAUUGAGUAAAAGAAAUGCCAUCAAUGAUCCCUUUUUCUAUCAACCUUAGAUAAUGAUAAUCAUUGUAAUAUUUUAGUGUGCUCCUUCCAGAUCUAUUUUUUGGAGGUGGCUUAUCCAGCAUACACCACACACACACACACACACAAAUACUAUAGUUCAAGCAACAUUAAGGUAUUGUGCUUGGCCAGGUCACGAGGUCAGGAGAUCGAGACCAUCCUGGCUAAUACAGCGAAACCCCGUCUCUACUAAAAAUACAAAAAAAAAUUAGCCGGGCGUGGUGGUGGGCACCUGUAGUCCCAGCUACUCGGGAGGCUGAGGCAGGAGAAUGGCAUGAACCCAGGAGGCAGAGCUUGCUGUGAGCCGAGAUUGCGCCACUGCACUCCAGCCUGGGCAACAGAGCAAGACUCCAUCUCAAAAAAAAAAAAAACUAUGCUUGUCCUAUGAACCUUAAAAUCUAGAACUAAAUAUACUUUAAUGGAUAUGGGGACAGAUUAUAAAUACCAAAAAGUCCCUGUGCAAUAAAGUUACUUAACUCUGUUGAGUAAAUAAACUCAUGGAAAACAAAAUGUUCACAAUUAGGAGAUGACUAGGUAGAGGAAGCAUAGAAAAGUGGAUACUGGAGAAACCAACUUCUGUAUACCUAAUUCUCUGAUUUUUUGCCAAAUAUGCAAACUUUUAAAAAAAUAAUUUCCUCCAUGGAAUUGCCUAUAGAGAGAGAUUAUGCUUUUAAAUUAGUUCUCUUUGUAAUUCAUUAUCUUGGUAUUCUGUUUUUGUGUAUGUAUUUUCAAAAAUUUGGUUUAUGUGAAUCUACAUUAGAAAGUGAUCUACUUUUCUGUGGUGAUAUCACUUUCUUUUGCCUUAGCAGUACUAAGGUAAUAUUUUGGGAAUUUUUCAAAGUUGUGAUUAGCUUUUCUCAAACAAUCCAAUCUCUCCAUAAAUGCCUUUCUAUCCAAACAGCUAUAUUCAAUUAGUAGAUAGAUUUCUAAUUUACAUAAUCAAUAUUAUUUUGUAUAUAUAUUUUUAAUCUGCUAUUUUCAGUUGCUCAUGAAAGAUCAUUUUUUUCAACUCAUUAAAUGUAUCUAGAAUGAAUGUAUUAUGAGAGUGGAGAUUUUCUGUCUUGUUUAUUGCCAUAUUCCAUUACUAGAGCAGAAAGAAGCUCAUGCAUGGUAGAUACCCAAUAAAUAUUGGAGAACUAACUUAAUAAAUGAACUCAUAUUUUUCUAACCAAUUGGGAGUGGUGAGUAGCAUAUUCCAUGUAGGAGCAAUAACUCAUUUUACCAAUUCUCUAUUAUUGGCCAUUAGUAACACCCAAUUUUUUACUUUUAUCAACAAAGCAAUGAUAAAUGAAUUUGAGGAUAUAUCAUUGGACACAUUUAUUUAGUUCAAAUUUCUAGAUUAGUUGUCUAUAUGUGUUAGAUUUUUGGAAUUGUCAAAUUUCUAAAGCAAACUUUAAAUGUCUAUUUAUAUACCAAAAUAUUGAGUCUAAAUAGGCAAUGAAAAUCAAAAUUUUUAUCAAAUAAACAUAUACACAAAGAAGAAAAGAAAAUAAUGCUGUGGUACUUUCACACCCAUAUAAUGAAACCUGACCCAACUAAAAUAUUAUGCAGCCUGAGUUCAGGGCUGGUAAGGUGACUGAGCUCUAGGCUACCCUUUUAUAGAGGCUGCCUUUUCAUAAGAUGUUAACCACCAAUCAGAGAUGACAUUGAUGGAAUGGCUUAAGAAGUUGAACAUGACAGUUUUGUCAGGUAAACUUCCCAGUGACAAACAGAAAGCUGGACAUAGCCUCAGCUCUGGAGGAUACCUCACAGAUAUAAUAUUUUGCCAAGACAGCUUUCUAAACAGUCUAAUCUUCUCAACCUGGUUUUCCCUGUCUUUGUCUAUCUGAAUAUUCAUUGACAGUGUGCUAAUGCAGAAAGUAAAGACAGCUUUUCACUCUACACCUACAUUGAAGAUCAUUUGGUAGUGCUAUCCUUUGUCGAUUUGUUAGACCAUCUCAGCUUUCUUUGAGAAAAGUGUCUGUUUAUAAGGAUGUACUGCCUUAAGGAAGCCAGUCCUUAGCUUUGGCUGGCUUCCUGUGUAAGCAUUACCAUGAUGGGCAUUAGUAUUCUCCACUUCUUAUUUACUGUCUCAAGGUUCUUAGAAAUGUAUGCAGUUUAGUGAACUAUAGCAUGAAAUUUUAGAGUAGGUUCAUGAUAGAUAGAUAGAUAGAUACACAGAUAGAUACAUAGAUUGAUAGCUAGAUCAUAGAUUUAUGGUAUAUAUGAGUUUAACUCCCAGGUCUUUCCAAAUGCUAUGGUGAUUCGUAUUAUCCUAGUUAUCUCUUUUGUUCAAAAUGUAAUGCUCUCCACUUAGUUGUUACAUGGAACAGCUUUUCCCAUAAACUUAGUGGUGUCAAAUUUCCCUCGUUAUAUAAAGAUGACAUUUUAAAAUUCUCUGACUGAUUCUUUGUGAUACACCUGAAUAAAUUUGAGCUUAAAAGUCACACCAUAUGCUAGCAGGGCUGGACACCUAGGUGUCCAUUUACAUUUAUGGCAUUCUUCCAAUUGCAACCAGCUACCAAUUAGUGGCAUUUUGAACAAACUGGAAGCAUUCAUAAGUCUAGAUUCUAGACUUACUCUGGCCUAUGAUGGCAAUUCCAGAUUUGAAGCUUUUUCCCUUGUUCUGCCUUCCCCAGUGUCUUCAUUCAUUGACUCAAGAAAUGAAUAGUAAGAUGCUAUUGUCUAGUAGAAACAAUACAAGACUUUAUUUUGUAGCUUUUGUUCAUUUUUCACUCAUUUGAUAAAUAUUAAAUAUCUACAAUUUUUCAGCCACUGCGUUCUGCUGAUAAAGAACAGACACCUCUUAUAGGUGUCUAUAUAAGGAACUAUAUUCCUUCCUCUUAUAGUUCUUGAAUGGGGACAACAAAUGUGUAACUUCGGUGUGUGAGAACUGCUAUGAAAGAAGUUCAAGUAAUGGUAUGAAAAAUUAGAUUAUGACUUCUUUAUAUAGGAUGGUCAGGAAAGGCCUCUCAGAGGAGGUAGCAUUUGAGCUAAGACCCAUAUGAUAAAAUGAGACAGCCAUGUGAAUACCUGGAAGAUGAGUAUUUCAAAUAGGAGGCACAAAGGCCUCCAGGUGAAAAGUAUUCAGCCUGGCCUGUGUAAGGGGUAGAAAUAAGGCCAGUGUGACUGGAGAACACAGAAUAAAGAUGAAAUACAGGGAAAUCAGGUGGGUGGUCUUAUGUAGGGCAGGUGAGAUGCAAUGGAGGGUGUGGAGUAGGGCAGGAGAAGUGAAAUUAGAGAAGACUGUUUUGAAGGUAGAACUAACCAUAUUUGCCAAUAAAUUGGAUAUGUCAAAAAGGUGGGCAAAAGAGGCCUUAGGAGUAAGACUCAUGUUUUUAGACUCAGCAAUAGAGAGAAUUGUACCAUUUAACUAAAAUCAGGUGGAAUGGUUUUGAAUGAGAAAAGAAGAAAAGCCGGAAUUAAAUGAUUAAGAAUAAUAUAUUUAGGGUUUGAAGCAUAUAAAGUUUAGAAUAUCUAAUAAACAUCUAAAUAUGAUAUGUAUAUAAGCAUAACUCAGAGAUAUUGCAAGUUGGAUUCUAGACUACUGCAAUAAAGAGAAUAUCACAAUAAAGUGAGUUACACAAUUCUGUUAUUCCCCAGUGCAUAUAAAAGUUAUGUUUAAACUAUACUGUAGUCUAUGAAGCAUGCAAUAACAUUAUGUCUCAAAAAUGCACAUACCUUAAUUUGAAGAUAUUUAGUUGUUAAAAAAUGCUAACAAUCAUCUGAGCUUUCAGUGAGUCACCGUCUUUCUUUUUGCUGGUGGAGUGCCUUGCCUUGAUGUUGAUGGCUGCUGACUGAUCAGGGUUGUGGUUGUUGAAGAUUUGGGUGGCUGUGGCAAUUUCUUAAAAUAAGACAACAAUAAAGUCGCCACAAUGAAAGAUUUCUCUGUAACCUGAAAUACUGUUGGAUAGCAUUUGACCCAUGGUAGAACUUUUUUUCAAAAAUGGAGUCAAUCCUCUCAAACCCUGAUACAGCUUUAUCAGCUAAGUUUAUUUGAUAUUUAAAUCCGUUUUUGCAUUUCAACAAUGUUCACAGCAUCUUUACCAGGAGUAGAAUCCAUCUCAAGAAACCAUUUCUUUUGCUCAUCCAUAAGAAGCAACUCCACAUAUGUUCAAAUUUGAUCAUGAGUUUGCCGCAAUUGUCACAUCUUUAGACUCCACUUCUAAUUUUAAUUCUGCUAUUUCCACCACCUCUAUGGUUGUUUUCGUCACUGUAAUUGUAUUAGGGUACCCUAGAGGGACAGAACUAAUAGGAUAGAUGUAUAUAUAAAGGGGAGUUUAUUCAGGAGUAUUGACUCAUAUUAUCACAAGAUGAAGUCCCACAAUAGGCUGUCUGCAAGCUGAGGAGCAAGGAAGCCAGUCAAAGUCCCCAAACCUCAAAAGUAGGGAAGCCAGCAGUGCAGCCUUCAGUCUGUGGCCAAAGGUCCAAGAGUCCCAGAGUUGAAGAACUUGGAGUCUGAUGUUCGAGGGCAGGAAGCAUCCAGCACGGGAGAAAGGAGGAGGCUGGAAGACUAAGCCAGUCUUGUCUUUCCAUGUUCCUCUGCCUGCUUUUAUCCUAGCUGCGCUGGCAGCUGAUUAGAUGGUGCCCACCCAGAUUGAGGGGGGUCUGCCUUUUCCAGUCCACUAACUCGAAUAUUAAUCUCCAUUGGCAGCACCUUCAUAGACACACUCAGGAACAGUACUUUGCAUCCUUCAAUCCAAUCAAAGUUGACACUCAAUAUUAACCAUCACAGUAGUCUUGAACUCCUCAAAGUUAUCCGUAAAGGCUGGAAUCAACUUCUUCCAAACUAUUGAUGUUGAUGUUUUGACCUCCUCCCAUAAAUCAUGAAUGUUCUUAAUGACAUCAAGAAUGGUGAAUCCUUUUAGAAUGGUUUCAAUUUACCUUGCUCAUAUCCAUUAUAAGAAUCACUAUCUUUGGCAGCUACAGUCUUACAAAAUGUAUUUCUUAAAUUAGAAGAUUUGAAAGUCAAAAUUGCUCCUUGAUUCAUGGGCUCUGGAAUGGAUAUUGUGUUAAAAGACAUGAAACCAACAUUAAUCUCCUUGUACAUCUCCACCAGAGCUUUUGGAUAACUAGGUGCAUUGUCAAUGGGCAAUAACAUUUUGAAAUACAUUUUUUUUUAGGAACAGUAGUUCCUAAAAUAUGCUUAAAAUAUUCAGCAAACCAUGCUGUAAAAACAUGUGCUGUCAUUUAGGCUUUGUUAAACUAUAUUUAGAGCAUAGGCAAAGUAGAUUUAGCAUAAUUCUCAAGGGCCCUAGAACUUUUGGAAUGGUCAAUGAGCAUUGGCUUCUAGUUACAUUCAUUGGCUGCAUUAUCCCCUAAGAUGGUCAGCCUGUCCUUUGAAACUUUGAAGCCAAGCAUUGACUUCUUUCCAGCUAUGAAAGUCCAAGAUGAAAUCUUCUUCCAAUAAAAAACCUUUUCAUCCACAUUGAACAUAUGUUGUUUGUUUAGUGUAGCCACCUUCAUCAAUUAUCUUAGCUAUAUCCUUUGGAUAACUUGCUGCAGUUUCUACAUUAGCACUUGCCGCUUCACCUUGCACUGUUAUGAUAUAGGAACAACUUAUUUCCUUAAGCUUCAUGGACCAACCGCUGCUGGAUUGCAACUUUUCUUCUGCAGCUUCUUUACCUCUCUCAGUCUUCAUAGAACUGAAGAGAGUCAGGGCCUUGCUCUGGAUUAGGCUUUGGCUUCAUCCUCUAUCCAGACCAUGAAAACUUUCUCCAUAUCAGCAAUUAAAUUGUUUUACUUUUUUUUUUAAUCAUUCAUGUGCUCACUAGAGUAGCACUUUUAAUUUCCUUUAAUAACGAUUCUUUUUUUUGCAUUCACAGCUUGACUAUUUGGUACUAGAGACCUAGCUUUUGGCCUAUUGCAGUUUUCAUAUGUCUUUCUUACUAAGCCUAAUCAUUUCUAGAUUUCGAUUGAAAGGGAGAGACAUGUGACUCUUCCUUUCAUUUAAACACUUAAAGGCCAUUGUGGGAUUAUUAAUAGGCCUAAUUUAAAUAUCGUUAUGCCUCAGGGAAUAGGGAAGCCCCAGCAGAGGGGGAGAGAUGGGGGAAAAACUGGUCAGUUGAGCAGUCAGAACACGUACAAUGUGUAUCUGAGUUUGCCAUCUUCUAUAGACAGAGUAUGUGACACCCCAAAACAAUUACAAUAGUUACAUCAAAGAUCACUAAUCACAGCUCACCAUAUCAGAUAUGAUAAUGAAAAUGUUUUAAAUAUUGUGGGAAUUACUAAAUGUGACACAGAGACACCGAGUGCGCACAUGCUGUUGGAAAAUGAUACCAAUAGAUUUGCUCGAUAUAAAGUUGCCACAAAACUUUAAUUUGUAAAAAAAAAAAAAAGAAAAAUGCAAUAUCUGUGCAAUUCAAUAAAGCAAAGCACGAGAAAAUGAAAUAUGCCUAUAGUAGUAUAUGUGUGUGUGUUUGAAGUGGCAAAUUAUACUUAAAGGCAAUAUUUUUAGUGUCCCAAAAUUGAUUUAAGCAAAAGUAUUAAUUUCUUUGCAGUAUUUUUUGAAUAAAUGUUUAGCAUCUUAAUGCAAAUAUUUUUGAGGUAACAUAUUGCUUUAAUACAAUUUCAAGCAUAGGAAAAGUUGUGAGAUUACUAUAGAGAGCAUCCAUAUACCCUUUUCCCAGAUUCACAAAUGUUUACAUAUUGCCUCAUUUACUUUAUCAUUCAUUUCCUUUCCAUCUACACACACAUACACACACACACACACACACUUACUUAUACAUUUUUACUAAACUGUUGUAAAUUUCAGACAUCAUACCUUUUUCCCCUUAACACCCCAGUGUAUUCCUCAGACCAAUAAGAUUAUCUUAUAUAAACACAGAACACUGAUUAAAAUCAGGAAAUUAAAAUUGAUAUAAUGCUAUCUUAUAAUUCACAGUCAUACUAAGUUUUUUUCAAUUGUCUUCAAAUUAUUUAAUAGUUAUUUUUCCUCCAGGUUCAGGAUUCAGUCCAGGAUCACACACUGCAAUUGAUUGUCAUGUCACCUUUGUCUCAUUUGUUUGGACUUGUUUCUCAACCUUUCUUCGUGGUUCUUAAUCUUGACAUUUUUUACAGAAUACAGGGAAUAGUUUGUAGAAUGAAACUCAGCUUGAGUUUAAUUUUUCCUCAUGAUUAGUUGCAGGUUAUGUAACGUCAGCAAGAAUAGCACAGAAACAAUGUGUCCUUCUCAGUGUAUCAUAUCAGGGAUGACAUUCAUUUGUUCUUUUAUUGGUGAUUUAAAUUUUCGCCACCUGGUUAAGGGGGUGUCUAAUAGAUUUCCCCAUCAUAAAGUUACUCUAUAUUCCCUUAGUAAUUAACUAAUUUGUAAGAAAAUAUUUUGACACACUCUAAAUAGCCUGUUUCCCAUUAAACGUUUACCCACUAAGUGUAAUAUCCAUUGAUGUUUCUUGUCUGGUAUUUCUUACAUUACUAUUAUGGUUACAAAAUUAUUUUUCUACCUUGUAACAUUUAUGAGUUAGCAUUCUCCUAAAAGAGCUUUUUACUUUUUAAUUAAUUUCAAUUUCAUUUUUUAAUUUGGAUGGCCUAUAGGCAUGCUCUCAUAAUAUUUUUAAUUCACUAGUAUAUAAGAUAAAAAACAGGACUUAUUCCUAAGAUUAAAAAACCUUUUAUUUUGUAUUUUUAAGAUCAAACUCGGUGCUAUAUGUCUUUGAAGUUUUGUGAGACUUUUGACAUUGAGAGACAUCAAUCUGUUGAUUGAUCAAAGAAUAAAACUCAGUUCAAAUAAGAGUUUGUCCACAUAGUCUAAAGAUAGUUUUACCUUGCCUACCAUCAGGAGACAAGAGUUGCUACUGAUACAGUUGAAAAUAGUAGAAAGUUGAUAUUUCCAAGGUAAUAGCAUAAAAUGUAAUCUCUAAUAUUUAUAUUUGCUACAGGGAAAUAUGUAAACAAAAUAACAAGGCUGGUAAAGAAAUGUGCAUAGCUCAGUUCUGAAGAUGCCAUCAAAUGGUCUUAUCUCCUGAAAGAUGCCUGAAGGUUAUCCCCCCAAAUUAAUUUUUGUUACCCUAAUAAAGACAUUAAUUUUUGUUUGAUAUACUACAUAAAGCUGAAAGUAAGAAGAAAAAAAUAACUCAGUAGAAUACCACUAUAAUGUUGGAUAUUAAGUGCAACUUAGCACCAAUUAGUUUAGCAAAUAUUUAUGUGGAGUAUUUUAUAUGCAACGGCAUCCAACCAAGCAAAAACAAUAAACUCAUUAUUUCAUCCCCUGAGCAUUUCAACUCCCUUAACUGCUCCAAACACAUAGAGGGAAUAUAAAAAUAUUUUUUAAGCUUAAAAAUAUAUAGUCUUAAAAACUAAUAAAAGUACAUCCAUAUAUAAACACCAUAAAAUAAAUGGAAAUUAAUGAAUGGAUUUCAACUGAGUGGUUAAAAGCAGGUAGAGACUUCCAUGAGAUUAGUUGCUAGGAGAGGUAUCAGGGAAUAAAUGCACCCUAGAUUAUAGCUAGGCUUAGUGCCGUAGUUUCAGCCAGCACCCAUCUCUCCUGCAGAGGGGCCUUAGCUACUAGACAGCUACUAUUCAUGCUGCCAGGGCCUAUGCCUUGUGUCAGGCUGCACUCCUGGAAAAUUCAGAGAACACAGAUAGAAAUCCCUAAACUAGUAACUGAGUUAAGCCCCCUGCCAGAUUGUUAAUUAGCAGUAUCCUCAUAGAAAUAAAGAUCAGGAGCUCCUCAAAGCCAACAUAUGAUCUUGUUUUGUACUAGAGCACUGGAGACAACCUGAAAAAAAAACAAAAAAAAGAUGACAAAACAAAGACAAAGAGAAAAUUGCGCAAAGGAAGAAGGAGGACAACAAGUGAGGGGUAGAGAAGAGAGGGAAGAAACAAAAAUAUCAACUUAAAAUUAGCCUGCAGCCAAAAUUUCCAAAAUUGAAUACCACAGUUUUGGUAUUCAAUUUUUGUUCAUGUAGUUAAUGAACAAAAUUAACAGUUGAAAGAUUAAUUUGAGAUGAAAUAAAAGUAACAAAAGUAAAGCACUUAAAUGUGCAUAGGAUCUUAAAUAUAUAAUUGAUGAAAAAACUUUUUAAUUAAAUACAUUAUAAGUAUUGGUGGAAAAACACAAUUUCUAUCCUUAAGGGGUUUAUGAUAAAGAUACUAUAUUACAUUACAUAUACAUGAAUAUACAUCAUAUAUUAUUAUCUAUGAUAUUUGUAGGCAUGUUUAUUAAAAGUUGGAAUAAUUCCUUCUAAUAUAUACCAACAUUUCCAUCAGAAAAUCUUAUUUGCAUUCCAUUUUAUCUUAUAGCACCUACAUUCUUUCUUAGGUGACUUCCUUCUCUUAGCAUAAUGCAUCUGAGAUUCAUCCAAUAUGUUUUUGUACAUAUUGGUAAUAAUGCAAUUAGUGUAAAUUCCUUUAUAUUGCAGAUUUAAUUAUAUAGAUAUACUAGGUUUUUAUUCAUACAUCAAUUCAAGGACAUUUGAUUUCCAGUUUUUUUUGAUGACCAUAUAUAUCACUAUAAACAUUUAUGUAAAAGUUUUUGAACAAACAGAUUUUUAUUUCACCUGGCUAAAUACCGAGGCGUGAAAUUCUAGAUUAUAUGGUAAGUAUGUGUAUAAAAAAUAACCAAACUGUUUUCUAAAGUUGCUGUAACAUUUGCUUUCCCAUCAUAAACAUAAGAGAGUUCUAGUUUUCAGCACUUGGUAUUGUCAGUAUUUUGGUUGUUUGUUAACUGUAGCCAUUCUUAUAGGUUUGCAGUGGUAUCUCAUUGUGGUUUUAAAUCUUUACUGAAUGACUAAUUAUGUAGAACAAAUUCUCUUGUACUCAGCAUCCAUACAUCUUUAUUCAGGUAUCUUCUUUUGUGAAAUCAUUUGUUCACUUUUAUCUAGCUUUUUAUUAAGUUAAUGUGAUUUAAUAGGUGUUUUUUCUUGCAUAGUGAAUAUAAAUCCUUUGUCAGAGAUUUGUUUUGUAAAUAUUCUUAUCUGUGGUAUGUCUUUAUAGUCUCUUAGCAUUAUAUUUCACAGAGGAAAAGUUUUUAUUCUUGAUGAAGUCCAAUUUAUUAAUUUUUAAAAAUGUAAUAAGUCAUGCUUUUCGUAUAGUAACUAAGAAAUCUUGCCUAACCCAAAAAGAAUUUUAUUCCAUUUCCUUGUAGAAGUUUUAUAAUUUUGGGGUUUUAUUUAAGUCUAUGAUCUAGUUUUAGUUACUUUUUUAAUCUCAUGGAAGGUAUGUGUCAAAGUUCCUCUUUUUUUCUUUACAUAUGGGAGUCCAAUUGUCCCAGCACCAUUUGUUUUAAGAGAUCAUUCUUUAUCCAUUGUAAUUGCAUUUGAACCUUGUCAAAAUGCAGUUGACUGUGUAUGUGCAGGUAUGUUUCUCAAAUCUUUUUCUGUUCCAUUGAUCUAAUUGUCUGUCUUGAGGUCAAUACCACACUCUCUGACUUUUUGUAGCUCUUUAGGCUUGAAACCAGAUAGUAUUUUUAUUUUUUAAGAUUGCUUUUGUUAUUCUAGUUAUUUUGCUUCUCCAAGCAAGUUCUAUAAUCAGUUUAUCUAUUACUAUAUAAAAUCCUUCAAGAUUUUGAUUGUGAUUAUUGCAUCUCUAUAUUAGUUUAAAAAGUAUUGACAUCUUCACAAUAUUUACUCCUUCAAUUCAUGAACACUGUACACCUCUUUUAUUUAGAUCUGUUUUGAUUUCUUUUAUCAAUUUUUUUACUUUGUUGCAUAUAGAUUCUUCAUAUUUUUCAGAUUUAUAUGUAACAUAUUUUAUGUUUUUGUUGUUGUAUAUCUUUUUAUUGUAAUUUCUAAUUAUUAAAUGCUAGUGUAUAGAAUUACAAUUGGUUUUUGUAUACUGGCCUUUUAUCACUAAACCUUGCUAAACUCACUAGUUCUAAUGUACCUAACUAACCUCAUUUUGUAGAUUAUUCUUCUGUAGAUUCUUCUUUUAUGGAUUUCAAAUGAUUUUUAAAAGAUAAACCUAUGAACUUCAAAUAAAGACAAUUUUUAUUAAUGUUAAAUAGAAGUGCUGAGAGCAAACAUCCUUGCACUGUUCCUGAUCUUAGAGGCAAAGCAUUCUGCUUUCAUCAUUAUGUAGAAUGGAAGCUGUAGAUUUUCAUAGAUCCCUUUUAUCAGGUUGAGGAAGUUUUCUUCUAUUCUUCAUUUUCAAAGAGUUUUUAUUAUGAAUGAAUAUUGAAUUUUAUUAAAAGCUUGUUUUUCAUCUGUUGAAAGAGACCUAUAACGGUUUUUCUUUUUUAGUGAUGUGGUUAAUUAUGAUUGAUUUUUUCAAUGUUGAAAGAGCCUUGCAGUCUUGGGAUGAACCCCACUUGCUCAUAAUUUGUUAUCCUUUUUGUGUUAAUAUAUUAGUAGAUUCGAUUUGCUCUCAUUUUGUUUAAAAGUUUAUAUCUACAUGGGCCGGGUGCGGUGGCUUAUGCCUGUAAUCCCAGCAUUUUGGGAGGCUGAGGCGGGUGGAUAACGAGGUCAGGAGAUUGAGACCAUCCUGGCUAACACGGUGAAACCCUGUCUUUAUUAAAAAUACAAAAAAAUUAGCCGGGCGUGGUGGCGGGCGCCUGUAGUCCCAGCUACUCGGGAGGCUGAGGCAGGAGAAUGGCUUGAACGCAAGAGGUGGAGCUUGCAGUGAGCCGAGAUUGCGCCACUGCACUCCAGCCUGGGCAACACAGCAAGACUCCAUCUCAAAAAAAAAAAAAAAGUUUAUAUCUACUUUCAUGAGAAAUAUUGUUCACUAGGUUUUUCCUGUAACAUCCUUUUUUGUUUGUUUUAAUAUCAGGGCAGCACUGGCCUCAUGAGAUGAAUUGCGAAAUGUUACUUUCAUGGAGAUUUUGUAAAAUUGGCAUUAUAUCUUUCUUAAAAGUGUGGAAGAAUUAAUUGUUAUAUUCAUUGUGCUUGGCAUUUUUUUUCUUGGAAGGAUUUAACUAUGAAUUGAGUUCCUUUAACAUAUAUCAAAGUAAUCAUGCUAUCCAUUUCUUCUUGAGUAAACUUUGGUAGUUUAUAGUUUAUACCUUUCAAGGAAUUUGCCCAUUGCAUCUAAUUGUUUGUAAUAUUUUAUUAUGAUGAUUUUCAUGUCUAAGUUCUGUCUUUCAUUUUAAUAUUGAUAAUUUGUAUUGUCUCCCUGUUUUUGGUUGGUAGGUCUGGCUAGAGGUUUAUCUUUUUUUUUUUUAAUCUUUACGAAGAACAAGGAUUUGGUUUUCAAUUACUCUAUUGUUUUUUUCACUUUCAUUGAUUAAUGCACCUCUUAUCUAUUAUACCUCCCUUUCCUUCUAAGGGUUUAAUUUGCUUUUCUUUACCAGUUUCUUAAAGUGGAGGCUUAGUUCACUGAUUCAAGAGGUUUUUUUUCUAAUAUAAACAUUUAAUGUUACACACCUUCCUUUAUACAUUUUCCUCUAAGUAUUGCUUUAACUGCAUCUCCCAAAUUUUGUCAGUGCUUUCAUUUUCUUUUAAUUUAAAAUAUUUUCUAAUUUUUCAUGUGAUUUCCUGUGAUUUCCUCUUUGACUCAUAGGUUAUUUAGAAGUGUUUUGUUUACUUCCAAAUAUUUAGUCAUUUUCCAUAUAUCUUUCUGUUACUUUUUUUUUUCCUUAGAGACAGAGUCUUGCUAUGUUGCCCAGGCUGGAGUGCAGUGGCUAUUCACAGGUGCAAUUAUAGUGCACUAUUGCCCAGAACUCCUAGGCUCCAAAAUUCCUCCUGCCUCAGCCUCAUCAGUAGCCUGGGAGAUGCCACUGUCCCUGACUUACUUUUCUUUAGUUUAAUAUUUUUUUAUGGUCUUAUAAUUCACUUGGUGUGAUUUUUUUAUUUGUUUAAAUUUGUUAUGAUUUGAUUUAUGGCCAGAAAAUUGUCUAACUUGGUGGAUAUUUUAUGUGUACUUGAAAAUAGUUUGUAUUCUGCUGUUGUUAGAAUAUUCUAUACAUGUUAAUUACAUAAAGUUGGUGGAUAGUAUUGAUUCAGGCUUCUAUAUCCUUAUUGAUUUUCUGUCUGUUAUAUUAAUUGCCAAGAGAGGAUUGUUGAACUACCCAAGUAUAAUUACAGAUUUGUCUAUUUCUUUAUUCAGUUACAUUAUUUUUUGCUUUAUGUAUUAUCAAAAAGAGUUUUUAGGUUCACACACACUUAGAAUGUUUUUCUUUUCUUAGUGAAUUGAUUUUUUUUAUUAAUCACAUUGUAAUGUUCUUUUUUAGCCCUGGUAAUAUUCCUUGUCUAUAUCACACUGCCUGUGGUGCUGAUGUCUUAUAACAUUGGUCUUUUUUUUUUUUUGCUCCUGGAAUUAAAACUGAACCUUAGUUUUUAAUAAGUGAAAUAGUAAAAGAACUCAGCAGACUGACUAAGAUGACAACUCAGAUGAGGUAACCAAGGUUUAUACCAAAGUAGUCUGCAGCAUAGUCAGGGCUAAAAUUCGUACACUGGGUAAUCUCUGGUUCCACCCAAACUAAAAUACAUCUGCUGAUAAAUUUGCUCUGAAUAAGCACCGUACUAUCAAGUUUUAAAGGUAUACGUGGCUCACGCCUGUAAUCCCAGCACUUUGCAUGGCAGAGGCAGGCGGAUCAUGAGGUCCAGGAGAUCAAGACCAUCCUGGCCAAUGUGGUGAAACUCCAUCUCUACUAAAAAUACAAAAAUUAGCUGGACGUGGUGGAGCAUGCCUGUAAUCCCAGCUACUUAGGAGGCUGAGGUGAGAAAAUCACUUGAACCAGGGAGUCAGAGGUUGCAGUGAGCCAAGAUUGCACCACUGCACUCCAGCCUGGCGAUGGAGUGAGACUCCAUCUCAAAAAAAUAAAAUAAAAUAAAAUUUAAAAAAGUAUGCGGUAGAAAUUUAAAGUCAGAUAUCUUGUAUCUGAGGUUCUCAGAAUGGAGAAUUCACUUCUCUUUGGUAACAGAUUACAGGGAACGAGUAAUUGUGCUGCAGCAAAUUGGGCCAAAAAUAAGUUAUAAAGUCAUUUUCUUUCUAAGAUAAACAUUCUCUUUCUAAGAUGAAACUGUUAACAAGGAAUAGCAAUUAUCUUCCUGGUAUCACUGUCACUGUUAUAACAAUGUAACUCUCAGAUAAAGCUACUAAUAGCUCCAGUUUUUGGUGCAGUUGCUUCAUGAAUUAGCUAUGAUUUCUUAGUUUUCCAGGUACUUCAAUCAGAAGCGUUCUGUUAAGCACCUCACACAUUGUAAGGAGUACGUGCACACAUUAAUGCACAGUACUUUUACAUUGUAAUAGGAACUAAACCCUACCUUUCAUUACUUAUGUAAGAGGAAUCAUGAAUGACAAACACGUUUGGCAUAAAGUCAUUAGUAGUCUGCCCUUUUAUUUGUUCUUCCAAUAAUGUCUUUACUUCUAAACUCACUAAUGUGGAUAAUAAAAACACUAGGCUAUACAUUAAGAAAUUAUUUUGUUGAAAUAUCCUUUAUCCCUGACUCUUCUAUUUCUUCUCAUUCAUAUUGCUAUAGGAAUACUGAAAUUUUUAUGGCUGUCUUUUUUUAGACACAUUUUAAGAAUCUGCUCAGAGAUAAUUUGAUGAAAUCUAUUUUUGGUCUCAGCAGGAGAAUCCUAAUUUGCAUCUCCUCAUGGGUCAUCAUUGCCUAAAUUGAUCUACACUGACCUGGUUCAUUUUAAAUCAAUUCAGGGUUUUUCUUUGUGCACACAGAACAAACGACCUGUUCUUCACAUGCUACAAAAUCAAUCCCAAAGAAAUUUAAAUGAUCUGGAUGGAUUCUUCAAAUAAAAUUGUACUGUGUUUUUCUGAUCAAAAUUGAGAGGAGUAUUGAGGUAAAACUAAAACACUGAAACGGAUUAACCAACCAGGUAGACAAAAAUCGUAUCAGUUGUCUGUAUACAAAAUACAUUUUACCCACCCAAUAUAUAAUUAUUAUUUUAUUAUCUGUUUACUAUAAAAUCAAUUUAUAUAACAUUUUGUAUUUAUUUUAUGGACAUGGAAUAUUUUUGGGGCAAGAUGAACAAUUGUUACUCUACUACAGUUGUAAAGAUUGCAUCUUUUAAAGUCAAGAUUCUGUAGCCAGCUUUACUUUAGAAGUAAGAUGGGAAAAACAUUCUAAACUGAAUAAGGGUCUAUGGUGGUUUUCUUUGCUAGAAUAUGUUGAGCUAUUUAGCUAGUCAACAAAAAUAGUAGCUGAAACUUCUCUCAAUAUCUUAGCACUUGUUUUUAAACAGAUUUUCUGUUAAAUAAAUUGGUGAACUAUAAGAAAAUAGUUAUAUUUCUUCUUGUAUUUAAAAAAGAUAUCAUACUUAAAAUAUAUUAAAUUUAUUGAGCUUGUGAAAUACCAAAUGUAUAAUAAGUGAUGUUCAUAACUACCUAUGAUACUAAUAAAUAAUAAAUGCUACAAGAAAAGUAAAGGGCUAUAAGAGUUUUUAGAGAGAAAGAAAGCUUCUUGCUGGAAGAAAUUAGUAAAUGUUUAAUUGAUAGCAAGGCACCUAAGUUAAACUUUAAGGGGAAAAUAGGUUUUGAACAUGAAAACAUUAAAAAAUCAUUCUAUUAAUAGGAAUAGUAUAAACAAAAUCAUUAAAGCAAAAGAUUGUGGAAAUGUUAUAAAAACAAUGACUAGAAGAUUAAGGCAUUAAAUGUAAAAGUUGAAGUGAAAUAGGAAGACUCACAGGACAAUGAUGACUCUUGCAAACCAACCUAAGACUUUGAGCUUUUCUUUUUUAAGCAAAGAGAUGCCAUCAAAGUUUUAGAGCUGUUGAAAUAUUUCCUAGAAUAACAGGAUUCAUUAAAAACAGCAACAUCUAAAAGGCAUAUUUUCAGGGAGUAUUUAGUUUCAGGCAUAUAUUCUAGGUUCUGGAGAUAAAAGAAAAUAUUCUUGCUCUCAAGGAAUUUGGGAUUUAAAGAAAGAGAUAGAUGCACAAACAAAAUAUGAAUUACAUGCCAAUUGCUUCUGUAACACAGUUGGAUACAGGGUGCUGAGGAAACAGAGAAGAUGAUAUAUCAAGGUAAUAGUAGCUCCAGAAACAAGUAAGUCCUAAACUAGCAGUGUCUUGAUACAAUAAGCAUUUAUUUUGUGUUCCAUCACAGCCAAAUGCGGUAUUCCUUCUGAGAUGACCUACCAUGUGGUCAUUUAGUCACCCAGGUUCUUUUCUUAGUGACCCAGGAUCUUUCCUUGGAGGACCUAGAGGACAGUAGCUCCACUGUCCUCUUGGAAGGCCUAGAGUAGUUCCACUGUCCUCUUGGCCUUCGAAGUCUUUUCCCUGGGUGAGGUAUACAUGCCUAACUAACUUAACUCAGAAGUUUCACACUUAACUCUUUUGAUGAGAACUAGUAGAACUAGAAAAGUUUCCCAGCUUUGUGUCCAGGAAAGACACAAUAAAGAUUCUGAUUAACUCAUUGCAAUCUCUGCCCCAAGAACACAUCUAACUGUGGAGUGGGGGUGGGUACAUCCAGGAGUGCUGGAAAGCACUGGUACAGUUGUAUGUGGCUGUUUACAUCCAGCCUCUGUUCUGAUUCAUUAGAAUCUGCCUGACACCUGUUUUGAUUCAUGUCCUUCAGUUGUUAAAUAUUUUGAUUAAUUUCCACAGUUUACCUGCAUUCGUGCUAAACCUGCAACAGGGAGAGUGAAUCCAGGGGCUCUAUUUUGACAUGAAUUAACUCGCAAUAGUUAAUAAGAUUGAAAAAAAAUGGAGAUUUGAAGAUAAUGAGAUAAUUUAGGAGGUUAUAUUUCAAAAGUACAGGUGAGAGAGAUGAAACCUGGACAGUAGGUAGUAGAGAUGAAAAGAAAAGAAAACAAACAAACAGGCAAAAUCUGAAAAAACAGCUCCAGGCAGCUAUUUGGAUGUGAAAAGCAAGAGACGGAGAAGAGCUAAAAAAUAAUUGCAUUAGUCCAUUCUCACACUGUUAUAAAGAACUACCUGAGACUGAGUAUUUUAUUCAGAGGAUUAAUUGACUCACAGUUCCACAGACUAUACAGGAAGUAUGGCUGUGAGGCCUCAGGAAACUUAUGAUUAUGGUGGAAGUGUGAAGGGGCAGCAAGCACGUUUUCACAUGGCAGCAGGAGACAGAGAGGAAAGAGGGAAGUGCCACACACUUUUAACCAUCAGAUUUCAUGAGAACUCACUAUCACAAUAACAAGGGGGAAAUAUGCGACAUGAUCCAAUCACCUCCCUCCACGUCCCUCACCCAACAUUGGGAGUUACAAUUUAACAUGAGAUCUGAGUGGGGACACAGAGCCAAGCUGUAUCAAUAAUCAUGAUAAAUAAAUAAAUGUCAGAGAUGUUGAGCCUAGGUAAUUCAGAGGUUCAUAGUGCUUUUACCAAAAUAGAGAAAAAGGAAAAAGAACAAAUUUUAGAAGAAGCCAUUAGAUUCUAAGCUUUUGGAAGGCAUGCAUCUGCUUUGUAGCUCCACAAUCUGAUACAGAACCGAGUAUACAGUAGGUGCUCCAUAGUUAUUAAUUUAAUUAAUGACUAAUGAAACCAAAUUACUUCAGUUUUAGAUACACUGAGUUUUUAGUGUCACUAAGACACUUGUGUAGAGAUGUCCAGAAAGUAAUUGUGAAGGUAGAAUCAGGUUAAAGAAAGGUAGUAAAUAAAGCCACAUAAUUACAAGAAAGAAUAUACUGGAAAAAAAAAAAGUCUCAGCAAAUAGAGAAGGAAUUCUUUUAAAGGGAUGAUUGGACAGCUGAUACAGAAACUUUAAGAGCUAAAAAGCAACCAUUUUAUUUCAGAAUUAUGGUAUAUGUUUCUUUUAUUCAUAGAUGGUUUUCUUUCAUUCAUUCACCUUUUUUUCUUUCCGAAUCGUUAUGGGUAUGAAUAUGUAACAGCAUGUACCAUGAAAGUACACAUUGUCUAUAAUCCAUCUUAAGAUCAUUGUUAAUUUGGCAUAUUUCCUUCAUGUCAUUCUAGGUGUGUAUUUUAAAAAGUCAAUGAAGAAUGUAUGAUUUGUUAACAGAUACCAUUUUUCAAUAUAAAAUUACCCUCUUUUAACUGUUUGAUGAUUUUGCCUUAAAUUCCACUUUGUCUGAAAAUAGAAUUGCAACUCUUGAUAGUUUAAUUUUUGGAGUUUCCUAACAAUCAUUUUCAUUUCCUUUUUUAAUAUCAUUUUGUUUCAACAGUCUCAUGUAAGCUACAUAAUAUUACUUUGAUUUGCUUUAAUUUUACUUUAGUUUUUCCUUUGCCUUCUAUGGACUUCAUGACAGUUUUAGUCACACUUUAUAUGUCUUGUGUUCCAUCUUUUUGUUUUGUAUUAUGUCUUGUUUUUACUGUGUAUUUUCUCUACUUAAAAGAGUUUUUCUUAUUUUGAUGUACCCCAGUGAUUUGGAGCUCAUAUAUUCUGUUUUUAAUUCUUAUGAUUAUAUUUACAUUUCUCAAAGAAAACCCUUCUAUGUCAAAAGUUUUCAAAAGUCAAUAAUAAAAUAUGUAUUUUGCAUCCCUUCCUCCUUUUGAUACUUUCCUCAUUCCAUGUGAGAGGGGGAAUGUACCACAUUUUUACUUCUUUUUCACUUCAUCUUCUCGUAUUUUAAAACUAUAAUAUAUAUGUUAAGACCCAUAUUAAUAUUAUUAAAUUAUGUUAAGCAUUUGUUAUUUUCUCUUUAAGCAACAUUCUGUUUUUAUUCAAUUUUGUAACCAAAUUUAAAACAAUCAUUUAGACUGAAAUUUAUGUUUAAUGUAAUUGAGUGUUCACUGCUAGUCUUUGUAGAACUAUUGGCUAGGUGUUAGUUUCUAGAACGACAUAACAGAUUGUUGCUCUUAAAGGGUUUAAGGUCUAAUGGCUUUCUGCCACUACUAUUACUCUUUGUUAUUCUCAUUCUCUUUUUUGGUUAAAAGUAGUAUUAAACUUUGAGUUACCUCCAUUCUUAAUCUCUUAGUUUAAGUACUUAUGCAAAGUAUAAGGAGGGUAAUUUAUUCUAAGUUCUUGAAAAUCUAAAAUUUCUUGGGAGCAAAAAUUAAUUAUUUCAUGAUUUUAUACUGCAAGGGAGAGAUCUAAGGCAGAUUUUACUUCUCUUUAUAUACAUAAACUAAUAUUUGCUCAUUUUUCUGUCCCAAUAUUUGUAGAAUAUUGCUUUUGUUCUUAUAGUUUAUUUUUUCUUUAGUAUUCAGUUUUUUGAACUGGUAUAGUAAGUCAUUUCAAUAUACAUAUUCAAGUCAUUUUUCAGCUCUAUAAGUUUUCUGUGGUAUCUUUGAAUACUUCUUCAAUGACAAUUUUUGAGGGUUUUAAAUUCAUAAUUACUGGAUUUAAUAACAUCUUUUUAUUCAAUUUUAAUCUCCCCUCUCUUCGUUUUCACUUUACAAUUUCCUCUGAGCUUUGGAGAUUAUCUUGAAUUGGCAAUCCAUAUCACUGAUUUAUGUUUUAUAAUGUGUUUUCUGUUUGUCUUUAACUGCUUUUACUAUGAUACUUUCACUUCUGCCAUGCUUCUUCAUUUCAAAUCUUUUUUUCCUCUGACUUUUCUAUUCUUGCGACUUUCAGCCCCUAUUUUAUAAAUAUUAUAACAUAUAUCCUUUUGUGUAUACCAAGUAAUUUUCUGUACCUUCUUUCCAGUUCCUGCAGCAAAUAAUUUUUAAAAGUUUAUUUUCUUCUGGAUAUAUGGAAUGAUGUAUCAUUCUUGCCUUGCAAUAAUUUAGAAGUUAUUUGUAGGUUUUCUUCUACUUGCCGUGUAUUGAAAAGAUCUCUAUAUAGGACUGGCAUUUGUCAACAGAUAAGAUUUACAAAUUGUGCUCGUGUCCCUCUCUAUACAUUUGUGUACUAGUCGAAGCCCCUACUUAGAUGUGCAGCUAGGUGGCACAGUGAUAACCACAGUGCCUAACCUGAUUCCUAGUCUCUGGUAGGCUUUUAUGCAAUGUGGCUGUGCAGGAAUGUAAGGAGACGGGUUUCUAUUCCCUCUUCCCCUCAGUAGAAAUUCAUUUGUUCUAAGAGGCAAUAUAAUGUCUACCAAUCAACUUUCUUUGAUUUCCUUUUAAAAUCAUUUUGUGUGACCUGCAAAAGCUAAUUAUAAAUAUAUAUAUAUACACAUAUAUAUGUAUGUGUAUAUAUAUAUUUAUUUAUGCAUAUAUAUGUGUAUAUAUGGCAAAAUUAGUACCUAUGUUCCUGGUGCCUGUCUCACUUUGGGAGCACAGUUACAGAGGGAGGUCUGCCUGCUUUCAUAUGAGCAUUUUCACCUAUUUUUAUUUAAAGAGUACGAGGGUCCUCAAUUCCAUUUUAAACUCUAGCUUUACUGACUCAGGUUACUAAAGAUCACCACAUAGAACAUAUAGAUUCUGGGUUAUACCCAGAAUUUUUUCAGGAUCCUUAACCAUAUUUAAAUGAAUGAGAAUGAGAGUGCUAUUAUAGGGAUGCAGCAAACCCAACAUAGCAGAUUUCAAAAGAAUGAAUAUUCUCCAGACUUUGUCCCUAUCUAUUAUUAGCAAUAAAUAAUUUCUAAUGUACCUCACAAUUAUGGAAGUAAGCCAGCCUGUCAAGACUUCACAGUUAAGAACUUAUGGAAUAAAACAGUGGUGGGAUAUUAACAUUUAGGGAUUCUUAGUGGUUUAGACUGAAGCCUAAAGUCUUACACCAUUAUAUCUUCUAACUAGCAACAGUGGAGUCACUCAGAGGCUGAAAACAGAGGAAAAAGAAUGUGGUCUCUUAUAUACCCCUGUUUCCCCAACCCCAAAUCUGUAUAGUUGCUAUGGCAAGCAAUUGCUUCUCUGGUAAGGCAACUCUUCCAAUCUUUCAUAAUCGCUGCCACCAUUCUAUUCCAGUAGGUCCAGAAAUGGUCCAAUAUCUCUAAGUAUUUCUUGUUUAAUCUGCACAGCUGUCAGAAUAAUUUUGAAACAGAAUUCUGAUCAUUUCAUUUUACUACUUAAAAACCUUCAAAGACAGCAAGUAUGUUGUACUGAAUGAAGGUAAAGACUUCAUAUGGAACACUCAGAUUCAGAGCCCCUACUCUGUGUCUCUGUCACUUCCACAUUCACUCCUGCCCUACUCUCCUUAAAGGUCAGAGGCCAGUGACACAUCCCAGGCAGGAGAUUCUCUGAUGUCUUUGUCCUGGACAAGAAAAAAGGCCUAUAGAUACUGACAUUAGAGAGUUCUGCCAAGGAAAUGGCUUCACCCCUAUGGAAGGCAGCCUCUAAGAUGGCCUCCGGUGAUCCUAGCCUCUGAUAUCUCUGUUCCUGUGUAAUCUCUUUCUUUGAAUGUGACCUGGACUUAGUGAUUCAUUUCUAAUGAAUAGAAUAUGGCAGAAGUGAUGAGAUACCACUUCCAAAGCUAGGUUGCAAAAAGAUUGUAAUUUCUCUCUUAGGGACUUUAACUUUCUCAUUCACUCACUCCUCUGAAAUAAACCAAUUGUCAUGUUGAGCUGCUCUGAUGAGAAGCUCAAAUGGCAAAAAAAGUCAUGUCUUUGAUCGCCAGCCAGCAAAAACAUGAGGCAUGUCAAUAAUCAUGUGAAUUAGCUUGUAAGUGACUCUUCCCAUAGUUGAACUUUGAUGUGUCCGAAGCCUCUGACAACAUCCUGACUUCAACCUUUGGAGAGACCCUGUGCCAGAGACCAUGGCCCAAAAACCUGAAAUGGUAAAUGUUUUUUGUUUUAAGUUGUUAAUUAUGGGGUAAUUUGUUAUGCAGCAAUAUAUAACUAAUAUAGUCACUACCCAGCCACUCCUGACGAAGGCCAUUAUUCAACAUGCCCCAGAAACCCAUAGACUCCAAUUGACUUUGUAUUAUUUUGUUCUUAAACAUAAAUAACUGAGAAAAAGAGCAUGAGGAAAAUUUGGUGGGGUUGUGGGGAAUGUGAUGGUUAUGUUCAUUUCCUUGAAUGUAAUAAUGGCUUCAUAGGCAUAUAUAUGUCAUAAAUAUUAAGUUAUAUAUUUUAAACAUAUGUAAUUUAUUAUGUGUUAAUUAGAGCUCAACAAAGCUGUUAAAAUAUUAAUAGAGAGAUAAGACUCAUCAAAUAUUUGAAAAACAAAAGACUCCAACAUAAUAGACAGGGAUCCAAAUGAAUAAAAUGUAGAAGGCAAUCAGAAAAUUUUGAAACAGUGCAGAAAAAGAAGAAAAAAAUGUCCAAAAAAACUCUAAAAUUAUUAUUUUCUAAGAAAUAAAUGAAAAAUUUUUCAGCCAUGGAAAAUGAGGGCUAUAGAAAAGAAUAGUAUAUGAAUAAGAAAGAAAGAGUUCCUAGACAUUAAAAACACAAUAGUGGAAGUUGAAAAUUCAGCAGAAGGUUUAGAAGAUAAAAUUGAAGAAAUUUCCCAGCAAGUAAAAUAAAGACAAAGAGGAGGAAAAUGGGAAAAAGAAGAUAACAAAAUGAGAGGUAUAGUCCAGACAUCUACAUUAGAAUUAAGGGAAUUUCAGAAAAAAUAAGAAGCAAAGAGGCUUACUUAUCAAUUAAUUUAUUUUCUAAUUUGAAGAACUAAAUACAAAUUUACACAUUUAAAUGGUCCAAAUUGUGCUCAAAAAUAAAUUUUAAAAGACCAACUAUAAGGCACUUUGUAUUAGUUAUCCAAUGCUAUGUAACAAAUGACCACAAAACGUGGCAACUAAAAACAACAUUUAAGGGGUAGAGCAAGAUGGCAGAAUAGAAGCCUACACUGUUCACCAUCCCCCACAGGAACACCAAAGUUAAACAACUGUCACGGAAAAGCAUCAUCACAAGAACCAUAGUACUUGAUUUUAAAUUCCUGUCACUGAAAGAGGCAUUAAAGAAGGCAGGAGAGACAGUCUUGAAUUGCUGACAGCAUCCCUUCCCAACCCCCCAGCUGUGGCUACAUGGUACAGAGUCUGUGCACUUGGGGGAGGGAGAGCUCAGUGACUGGGGGACUUUAGGUUGAACUCGGUGCAGCCCUGUCACAGUGGAGAGCAAAGUCAUACUCAGCCAGCGCCCACACAGGGAAGGAGAAUUUGGAUCAGCCCUAGCCAAAGGGAAAUCACUCAUCUCAGAGGUAAGAACAAACCUUGUCAUCAGGGGCUGAAGUGCUCUAGGGUCCGAGGUAAACUUGAAAGGCAGUCUAGGACACAAGGACUACAAUUCCUAGGUAUCUCCUUGUUCUGGGCUAGGCUCAGAGCCAGUGAACUAGGGUGGCACAUGACCUAAGGAGAUACCAGCCAGGGCAGCGAAGGGAGUGCUUGCAUCACCCCUUCCCCAACCCCAGGCAGCACAUCUCUCAAACAAAAGCAAUUCCUUCCUUCUAUUUAAGAAGAAGAGAGCAAUAAGUAAAGAGGAAUUUGUCUAGCAUCUUGCAUACCAGCUCAGCCACAGUAGCACAGGGUACUGGGCAGAGUCAUGAGACUCCCAUUCGAGGCCCUAGCCCAUGAUGACAUUUCUACACACAUCCUUGGCCAAAAGUCACUCCACUGCCUUGAAAGGAAGGACCCAGUCCUGGCAGGAUUAAUCACCUGCUUACUAAAGAGCCAUUGGGGCCUGAAUAACCAGUAGUGAUAUCCAGGUAGUACGCCGUAGGCUGUUGGCUCUGAGAUAAGUUGACUUCAGAUGUGACCCAGAACACUCCCAGCUGUGGUGGCUAUGCUGAAAGACUCCUUCUGUUUGAGAAAAGCAGAGGGAAAGGUGAUGAGGACUUUGUUUUGCACCUUAGGUACCAGCUUGGCAACAGUGGUGUAGAGUAACAAACAGGCUCUUGGUGUCCCCAAGUCCAGACCUAGGCUAUUGGACAGCAUUUAUGGGCUUGUCCUGGGCCAGAGGGGAGCCCAAUACUGCACUGAGAGGUGAGUCCUAGGCGUGGGAUAAUUCACCACAAGCUGACUGAAAAGCCCUUGGUCUUUACAUCAACAUCAGUGGUGGCCUGGCAGAAUUCCCCAUGGGCCAGUGGUAUUAGUGGCCACAAGGAGAGGCUCCUAAGCCUGUGGAAAGAGAGGGAAAGAACAGGAAGGAUUUUGCAUUGUAGUUUGAGUGCCAGCUUGGCCACAGUAGAAUAGAACAUCGGUAAACUUCUAAGGUUUUUUGCUGCAAUCCCUGGCUUCCAGAGAGCAUCUCUGGACCUUCCCAGGAGCGGGGGGAGCACAAUGUCCUGAAGGGAAGGACACAAACCUGGCUGACAUUACCACUUGCUGAUCAUAGAGCCCCACGGCCUUGAAUGAACAUAGGUGGUAGCCAGGCAGCGGUUACAGUAUGCCUUGGGUGGGACCCAGUGCUGUGCUGACAUCAGGUUGACCCAGCAUAGUCCCAGUGGUGGUGAACACAAGGGUGCCUAUAUUACCACACCCCUGGUUCCAGGUGCCUUAGCACAGAGAGAGAGCCUCCAUUUGUUGGGAAGAAAGUAAGGAGAAAAGACAAGAAUCAGGCUGGUAAUCCAGAGGUCAUCUGGAUUUUAUCUAAGACAAUCAAGGAGGUGCUUUUACAGGUCUAGAAAAAUCACAGUGCUAUUGGGCUUGGGAUUCAAAUCCCUUUGAAUACCUGGAAAGCCUUCUCCAGAAGGAUGACCACAAGAAAGCCCAGACUGUGAAGAAUACAAUAAAUACCCAACUUUUCAAUGCCCAGACACCAGUGAACAUCUACAAGCAUAAAGACCAUCCAGGAAACUGUGACUUCAGCAAACAAACUAAAUAAGUUACCAAGGACAAAUUCUGAAGAAACAGAGGUAUGUGACCUUUCAGACAGAGAACUAAAAAUAGCUGUGCUGAGGAACUCAAAGAAAUUCAAGAUAACACAGAGAAGGAAUUCAGAAUUCUAUCAGAUAAGUUUAACAAAAAGAUUGAAAUUAUUUUUUUAAAUCAAGCAGAGAUUCUGGAGUUGAUCAAUUCACAUACUGAAGAAUGCAUCAGAGUCUCUUAAUAGCAGAACUGAUCAAGCAGAAGAAAGAAUUAGUGAGCUUGAAAACAGACUAUUUGAAAAUCAGUGAUGAGAGGAUAUGAAAGAAAAAAAGAAUAAAAGGGAAUGAGUAUCUACCUACAAGAUGUAGAAAAUAACCUCGAAAGGGGAAAUCUAAGAGUUAUUGGCCUUAAAGAGAAAGUAGAAAAAGAGAUAGGGGUAGAAAGUAUAUUCAAAGAGAUAUAUCAUAGAACUUCCCAAACCUAGAGAAGAUAUCAACAUUCAAGUAAAAGAAGGUAAUAGAGCACCAAGAGAUUUAACCCAAAGAAGACUUCCUCAAGGCAUUUAAUAAACAAACUCCUGAAGGUCAAGGAUAAUGAAAGUGUCCUAAAAGCAGCAGGAGAGAAGAAGCCACAUACAUGGAGCUCCAAUACCUCUGGCAACAGACUUUUCAGUGGAAACCUUACAGGCCAGGAGAGAGUGGCAUGACAUGUUUAAAGUGCUAAAGGAAAAAAAAAACUAAUAAUAACCUUUUACUCUAGAAUAGUAUAUCUAGUGAAAAUAUCCUUCAAACAUGGAGGAAAAAUGAGGACCAUCCCAGUAAAACUGGGGUGGUUAUUUAGUUAGUUAUAAAUUUAGUUAUUUGUAAACUGUUAGACUGAGAACCUUAGCACCUCUCUGGCUGUUAGCCAAAGUCCAUCCUCAUUCCAUUGCUUGUAGGCUUCUCCAGUAAGGCAACUCAAUUUAUCACAGCAUAAAAGCCAAGAAUUAAGAGUUAGCUAGUAAGACAGAAGUCACAAUUAUAGAAACGCUAUAUCAUCAUCUUUGUCAUAGUCUGUAGUCUUCUAACAAUUAGGUUAGAAGCAAGUCCUUAGGCCAGCCCAUACUCAGGGAAAAGGACUUACACAAGGGCAUGAGUUCUAGGAGGCAGGGAUUAUUGGUGCCAUCAUGGAAAUCUGUCUCCCCGCACUUCACUGUGAACAUGGAAGAACUAGGAAAAAGGAAACUUGAAACUUCCUGAGACAGAGAACAUUAGCAAUCAUAUAACAUUUCAUGUGUUUCUUAACUUUUCCUGGAAGAUUUCCUUGCAAUUAUGUUAGGGUAGUGCUUCUCAACCAUGGGUAAUUUUGUCUCUCAAGGGACCUUGUCAAUAGAAAUCUUCGAUUAUCAUAGUAGGGGAUGUUACUGACAUCUAGUGGGCAGAGGCCAGAGCUAUUGCUAAAUGUCUCACAAGGUACAGGACAACCCCCACAGCAAAGCAGUAUCUAAGCCCAAAUAUCAAUAUGGUCAAGAUCCAGAAACCCUGGAUCCAGAGACUUGCAUUUUUUGGCAAGAACCAUGAACAGAAGUGACAUACCUGCGUCAAAGCAGUUAGGAGCCACUGAGUCUUCUCCACAUCUUCCUUCCUCAGUCAAAAUGACCUUGAAAGCCACAUGUUGAGAUGGCAGUAUUAAAACAUGGAAAGAGCCUAGAUUCCUAGGUCAUCAGAUGGAGGCAAGCUUCUAUUGAACUGCAUCGGACAUGUGAGCAAGAAGCAAACAUAUGCUUUGUUGAGAUUUCAGCAUUUGUCUGUUGAGAAAAUUAGCAAUAAAUAAGUGGAUGAAACUAUACACGCCUGAAAAUCAGGAUGGCAUUGGACUCAAAAGCAGCACCAGAGGCAAGAAGAUAGUGCGUAGGUUGCCUCAAUACACUGAGGAAAAGUAACAUCCACUAUAGAAUUAUAAAUAUGCCUAGUUCUUCAAAUAUAUUUGGUUCAUAGCAUUUGGAAAAUAGAAAACAUUUCAUACAAAAAUUUUUUUCAGAAUCUAUUCUCUUCUUCAAAUUGAGUAGUAAGAGUUGAGAUAACAAAUGAUACUUGAAUAUAUGUCUGCCCCCAAUCUAUCAAAUAUGAGGGUAGAAUAAAGACAUUUUCAAAUAUCUUUCCAUAUUUGAAAUAUCAUUUCAAAUAUCAAAAGGUUUCAGAUUGUGUACUGUCUAUUCACCAUGUCUUAAGAAGCUUCUUAAGAAUAUAUGCCCCCAGAUGAAGGGGAUAAAUCAAGGAAAAAGAACAUAGUGGCGUACAGAAAGCAGUGAUCCUAACAGAGAACAGAGGUGAGAACGGAGUAUUUCCAGCAGAAUGGCAACACAGCAGGCUUAGGGAGCAACCAGUUUCAAUUGGUGUAAGAAGACACUUAAGCAACAUAUUAAAAAUAGAAGUUACACUUGUUCUCCACCAACCUUAUCUCUUAAAGGACACUUUGAUACAUCUACUCACUUAAGUCAUAUGCAUCAUUAUUCCCACUAGCUUUAUACUAACUCCUACUCAUCUUUCCAGAUUUAUUUCUGAGGUAUUCUGGAGCCAAUCCUCUGCCUGGGGGCACAUUAUGUUUUCUCCUACUUUGUGAAACCAUUUGCAUAACAAAAUUUUACUGUGUCAUUUGGCAUGUCUUUUACAUCAGUCACAUCACAGUCCUGUUGUGAUAACCACACAGAUUAAUAUCUGCUAUGGCAUUGAUGAAAAGACGUUGAUCCUAAUUUAUAGGUUAAUAUAGAGAAUUUUAGAUAAACUGCAGUAGACAAUGAUUCUGUAAUGCUAGGGUGACAGCAGAUCAUUCUUGGCCCAGGACUAUAAAAUUCUGUGUCUGCGAAUGGGGCAGGAAUUGCUUCGGUGGAACAUAGCCACUGGGUAUUUUGACUCCGUGAAUUGAAAAAGAAUUAAAAUGCAAAAAGUCUUGACUUUUUGAGUUUCUUAGUUGCUUUGCCAGUCUCUAUACAAUCUGAAAGCGACACCUGAAACUUUCCAACAGGAACUGUAUAUGGAAACCACCAGAUCAAAAGACAGGCUGGCAAGGAAAAGCGAGACUGAAACUGUAGAAGCUAGUGUCUGAGACAGAGCCCCUUGGGAUGGGAUCACUAGGAAUGGCAGAAGCCCAAGGACCCUGGAGCCUGCCCUUGACUGGCAGUUCUUCAUGCCAAGCAGAAAUGGGAUAAUUGCCCAGGCUGUAGAUGUUGGAGGGGUGACAUCAGAACAAUAUUUUAACUCUCAGUGAGCAGACUGCAUCUCUAGAAUGUUUUAAAAUACAAGGAACUAUAAAACGAGAUUAAUUAAAUAGUUACAAUAUAUUUUUAAUGUGGGAGUAGGUAAUGGCAAAAAUAAUAGUCAAGUUGAGAGCAAGUUCUUUACUAACUUCCCUUUAAAAAGUAGCCAAGGAAACUGUUUCAGUGUUAGAUUUUUUUUAACUUUGUAUAACUUUCUUGUAAAUAUUUGUGCUUUAAAUCUUGUGCUUUAUAGGCAGCUGUAAUCUUGAGGCUUUGUGAUUUGGGCAAGCUAAUGAGGGUUAAAGACAGUAAAUCUAAUGUUUGAACUAUAGUCAGGUAUGACUUAUUACUUGUACCAAUCAGUCCUCCAAAACAGAAAAUCAGAAUUAUUCAAUUGAGAUAAAAAUAUCUUAUUUAUGUGCCCAGAAAAUUAUCUAUUUUUUAACCUCCUGCUUUAAGAUGCAUAAGAGAAUACAUCUGACCAGGUGGAGUUCUGAGUGUGAAAGUUAUAGUUAAAUGAGUCUCUAAGGAUUUGAAAACUUUUAGUUUCCAGGAUGAUCCAUGGUUUCUAAGAAUACUGAAAUGAAAUGGAAUUGGGAGAAAUACUACCGAAGAAUUAGAUGGCUCUACUUCAGAUCUAAUUUUGUUAAUGAUAAACUGUCGUUUUUGAACUGAGUUGUAGGGGAGGAACUGACGACAUAUUCAGGGACUUUGAAAGCCUUGGAAUAGUUCUGGUCCGUUUGAAUUCUGACUUCUGGUCUUGGUUUCUGCAAAUUCUGCUUGCGGAAAGUAAAUGCAUGAUAGGAAAGGGGUUGUUUUUCUUUUCCCUUACCACCCUAGUAAAAUAUGGAUAAAUAAUAUAGAAAAUAAAAGAACCUUAUAGAAAGUAGCGUGACAUUAGAUGAACAAUGUUAAGUGGAGGGCAAAUCUAUUUUCUUAAUGAAAAAAAGCAUCACAAUUUGUUAGUAAUCUCUGCACUCAGAUCAUGAGAAUGGAGAGGUAAUUUAAGUGGCCCUUCGCUGGGACCUGGAGAGGCAGAGCCAAGUUAGGCCUUAAAGCCACAGGUAGGUUUUGCCCCUCUAUAUUUCUGAGCAGACACAGCCCAAACCUGACCAAGCUGAAGGAAGGCAGAGGAAUAUGAUGUAGUGUCAAACCCAGUUGGUAUAGGAGAAAAAAAGCCUAAGAAAAGGGAAGAUGAGAAAGCAGGUUUGGAGUUGAAUUUACUCAAAAUACUGAAUGCCCAAAAGGGAAAAAAACAGACCUCUGCCUUGAGGCACACUGAGGUGAGAUCAAGUUCCUUGGUGUCCCCAGCCUGUGAGGCCGGAAACCUUAAUACAAGAAAUGUUAGAAAGCCUGGGGAUGGGGCCACACAGUAGCUUCAGAUAGUACUGCUGCCUGGCUAAACAGAGAUGCUACCUUAUCCACUGAAAACCUUCAGGACUACCAGCCUCUUAGUAGAUAGUUUAUUAAAUUCUUUGGGAUAGUUUGAGUAAUAGCACCUGAGAUAUUCCUUAGGCAAUUAAUAUUGGCCCUAUCUAGGUACAAGAAGCAAGCCCAAUAUAUGGCCAGCCUGAUUGGAUUUUGUCAUAACUGUAUUUUACACUUAAAGAUCUUAUUCUUCGUAUUCAUCAAAUUACCUAUACAAAAGUGCCUUUGUAGCUCUUGUUCUUGGUAAUUAUGCAGUUAUUAUAGAAGGAAAACUGGUGCUUCAUAACAUUUAAUUCAUACUAAAAUAUGCUUCUUACCUAUGUUUUUCUUUUUAAUUGUUAACUGUGUAAUAUAUAUGAAGUAUAUAAUAUGCAUGUACUAGUAGUAAUGAUAAUAAUAUAAUAAAACUAGCACCAAAGUUCUCACCACUCAGAUUAAGAAAUAAGUAUUACUGAAACUGGAAACUCUUUUCAUAUCCUUCCCUAAUCACUUGGCUCUCCCUUCCUUACAGAAGGAACAACUAUCUUGAAAUGUUUAAUUCAUUUUGUUGCUUUUCUUUAUAGCCUUUCAUAAAUAUAUGCAUCUUUAAAAUUGUAUUUUUUAUAUUGUUUUGAAUAUUUAUAAAUAAAAUUACACUGUAUGUUUUUUUCUAUAAUUUUGUUUUAGAUCCAGAUUUAGAUUACAUGUGGAGGCUUGUUACAUGGGUAUACUGCAUUUCUAUAUGCCAGCAAUGAACAAUCUGAAAAAUAUAUCAAUAAAGCAAUCCCAUUAAUAAUAGCUACAAAUAAAAUUAAAUACAUAGGAAUUAACCAAAGAAGUAAAAGAUUUCUGCAAUGAACACUAUAAAACACUGAUGAAAGAAAUUGAAAAAGACACAAAAAAUGAAAAGAUAUUUCAUGUUCAUGGAUUGGAAGAAUUAAUAUUGUUAAAACAUCCAUACUACCCAAAGCAGUCUACAGAUCAGUGCAAUCCCUAUGAGUAUACCAAUGACAUUCUUCACAGAAAUAUGAAAAAAAAUUCUAAAGUUUAUAUAGAAUCACAAAGUCCCAGAAUAGCCAAAGCCAUCCUGAGCAAAAGGAACAAAACUCGAGGAAUAACAUUACCUGACUUCAAAUUAUACUACAGAGCUAUAGUAACCAAAAAAGCAUGGUACUGUCAUAAAAACAAACAGACCAAUGGAACAGAGUAGAGAGCCCAGAAACAAAUCCACAUAGCUACAGUGAACUCAUUUUCAAUAAAGAUGCCAGGAAUACGUUGGGGGAAAAGACACUCUCUUCAAUAAAUGGUGCUGGGAAAACUGGAUAUCCAUAUACAGAAGAAUGAAACUUGAUCCCUAUCUCUUGCCUUAUGCAAAAAUCAAAUCAAAAUGGAUUAAAGACUUAAGUCUAGUACCUCAAACUAUGAAAUUACUAACAGAAAACAUUGAGGAAACUCUCCAGUACAUUGGUCUAGGGAAAAAUUUAUUGAGUGAUACUUCACAAGCACAGGCAACCAAAGGAAAUGUGGACAAAUGGGAUCAUAUAAAGUUUAAAAACUU